AGAAGAAAGUGUCUCUCUUCCUGCUUAAACCUCUGUCUCUGACGGUCCCUGCCAAUCGCUCUGGUCGACCCCAACACACUAGGAGGACAGACACAGGCUCCAAACUCCACUAAGUGACCAGAGCUGUGAUUGUGCCCGCUGAGUGGACUGCGUUGUCAGGGAGUGAGUGCUCCAUCAUCGGGAGAAUCCAAGCAGGACCGCCAUGGAGGAAGGUCAAUAUUCAGAGAUCGAGGAGCUUCCCAGGAGGCGGUGUUGCAGGCGUGGGACUCAGAUCGUGCUGCUGGGGCUGGUGACCGCCGCUCUGUGGGCUGGGCUGCUGACUCUGCUUCUCCUGUGGCACUGGGACACCACACAGAGUCUAAAACAGCUGGAAGAGAGGGCUGCCCGGAACGUCUCUCAAGUUUCCAAGAACUUGGAAAGCCACCACGGUGACCAGAUGGCGCAGAAAUCCCAGUCCACGCAGAUUUCACAGGAACUGGAGGAACUUCGAGCUGAACAGCAGAGAUUGAAAUCUCAGGACUUGGAGCUGUCCUGGAACCUGAACGGGCUUCAAGCAGAUCUGAGCAGCUUCAAGUCCCAGGAAUUGAACGAGAGGAACGAAGCUUCAGAUUUGCUGGAAAGACUCCGGGAGGAGGUGACAAAGCUAAGGAUGGAGUUGCAGGUGUCCAGCGGCUUUGUGUGCAACACGUGCCCUGAAAAGUGGAUCAAUUUCCAACGGAAGUGCUACUACUUCGGCAAGGGCACCAAGCAGUGGGUCCACGCCCGGUAUGCCUGUGACGACAUGGAAGGGCAGCUGGUCAGCAUCCACAGCCCGGAGGAGCAGGACUUCCUGACCAAGCAUGCCAGCCACACCGGCUCCUGGAUUGGCCUUCGGAACUUGGACCUGAAGGGGGAGUUUAUCUGGGUGGAUGGGAGCCACGUGGACUACAGCAACUGGGCUCCAGGGGAGCCCACCAGCCGGAGCCAGGGCGAGGACUGCGUGAUGAUGCGGGGCUCCGGUCGCUGGAACGACGCCUUCUGCGACCGUAAGCUGGGCGCCUGGGUGUGCGACCGGCUGGCCACAUGCACGCCGCCAGCCAGCGAAGGUUCCGCGGAGUCCAUGGGACCUGAUUCAAGACCAGACCCUGACGGCCGCCUGCCCACCCCCUCUGCCCCUCUCCACUCUUGAGCAUGGAUACAGCCAGGCCCAGAGCAAGACCCUGAAGACCCCCAACCACGGCCUAAAAGCCUCUUUGUGGCUGAAAGGUCCCUGUGACAUUUUCUGCCACCCAAACGGAGGCAGCUGACACAUCUCCCGCUCCUCUAUGGCCCCUGCCUUCCCAGGAGUACACCCCAACAGCACCCUCUCCAGAUGGGAGUGCCCCCAACAGCACCCUCUCCAGAUGAGAGUACACCCCAACAGCACCCUCUCCAGAUGAGAGUACACCCCAACAGCACCCUCUCCAGAUGAGAGUACACCCCAACAGCACCCUCUCCAGAUGCAGCCCCAUCUCCUCAGCACCCCAGGACCUGAGUAUCCCCAGCUCAGGUGGUGAGUCCUCCUGUCCAGCCUGCAUCAAUAAAAUGGGGCAGUGAUGGCCUCCCA